AGGUGACGCUUCCGGCGCAGAAAAAUGGCAGCCGCCGCUCCGGACUCACGUGUGAGUGAGGAAGAAAACCUGAAAAAGACCCCAAAGAAGAAGAUGAAAAUGGUAACUGGAGCCGUAGCGUCGGUGCUGGAAGACGAGGCCACAGACACUUCUGAUAGUGAAGGUUCUAUAGGAAGCUGUGGAUCGGAAAAGGACCACUUUUAUUCUGAUGAUGACGCAAUAGAAGCUGACAGUGAGGGUGAUGCUGAGCCCUGUGACAAAGAAAAUGAAAAUGAUGGAGAAUCAAGUGUUGGGACUAAUAUGGGCUGGGCAGAUGCUAUGGCUAAAGUCCUCAACAAGAAAACUCCUGAAAGUAAACCUACUAUUCUGGUCAAAAAUAAGAAGCUGGAAAAGGAAAAAGAAAAGUUAAAGCAAGAAAGACUAGAGAAAAUAAAACAGCGUGAUAAGAGGCUGGAGUGGGAAAUGAUGUGCAGAGUAAAGCCAGAUGUUGUCCAAGACAAAGAGACAGAGAGAAAUCUUCAGAGAAUUGCAACAAGGGGUGUGGUGCAAUUAUUUAAUGCUGUUCAGAAACAUCAAAAGAAUGUUGAUGAAAAGGUUAAGGAAGCUGGAAGUUCUAUGAGAAAGCGUGCUAAGUUGAUAUCAACUGUUUCCAAGAAAGAUUUCAUCAGUGUUUUGAGAGGGAUGGAUGGAAGUACAAAUGAGACUGCUUCAAGCAGGAAGAAACCAAAAGCCAAACAGACUGAAGUGAAAUCAGAAGAAGGCCCAGGUUGGACGAUCCUACGUGAUGAUUUCAUGAUGGGAGCAUCUAUGAAAGACUGGGACAAGGAAAGUGAUGGGCCAGAUGACAGCAGACCAGAAUCUGCAAGUGACUCUGAUACAUAAAGCAUCAUAGGAAAUACAAUUGCAGUCGUUUUAUUUUUUCUAGAAAAAUAUGUCAUCCUCUGAUAGUUGGGGAAUUAUAAGGAUACCAUUUGUAAGAAAGCCAAAAGACUUUUGCCAGAUUUCAUAUUUCCCCUUUUCAUGUACACUUUAUAUAUACUUCAUUAAAAUUAUAUUUUAAACCCUUGUAUAAUUUUAAGCAUUGUUCCUCAGAACAUUUGUAAAAGGAUAUAUUUCUGCUUGACCAGCGAGAUGUGCAUUUUGCCAGGAUCAUAUUGGUCAUGUCUAUUGGUGUAUUAUUUCAGUAUCACCAAUGUUUUCAGAAAUACAGUACUAAUUCAUCAUUAAACUCUUUGAAGUUAAUAUUUUUCUGCCUUCUAACUUAUAGACUCAACUAUGUAUCUGUAGUUUUUGGGAAUGGUUGGUGUUUUUUGCUUUGUGUUGGGAAGUUAUUGAGAAAACCUAUAUAAUAAAAUUUAAAAUUAUAGUUUUUCAGAUUUUGGGUCGUGAUUUUAGUUUUAGGUAAUCUGGAAGAUAUGAUUUAAGAAACAACAGAUUUCAACUUUUUUUUUUUUUUUUUUUUUUUUUUUUUUUUUUUUUUUGAGACGGAGUCUUGCUCUGUGGCCCCGGAUGGAAUGCAGUGGCGUGAUCUCGGCUCACUGCAAGCACCGCCUCCCAGGUUCACGCCAUUCUCCCACCUCAACCUCUCAAGUAGCUGGGACUACAGGUGCCUGCCACCACGCCCAGCUAAUUUUUUGUUUUUGUAUUUUUAGUAGAGACGGGGUUUCACCAUGUUAGCCAGGAUGGUCUCAAUCUCCUGACCUCGUGAUCCACCCGCCUCGGCCUCCCAAAGUGCUGGGAUUACAGGCGUGAGCCACUGCGCCCGGCCCAGAUUUCAACUUUUAUUUUAUUUCCUUUCAUUUAUUAAAUAAUAUAAAUAAUGACAGAUUUAUUUUAGGUGUUAGCCUAUUUUUGCAUGAGAGAUUUACAGAGGUGGAAAUUCUCAUGCUUAACUUAUGCAAUGAGACAAUUUCUCAGGAAGCAAGUUUGACAUGCUUUAGUCUCUCUCUUCUUUUUUUUCCUCCCAAAUAUUUGAGUUAGCUUAAAUUCUUUUUUAUGGACUGCCCAACCAGUGAAUUGAUGCACUUAGACAACAAGUAAUCUGCAGCAGAAUAUUGCAUCCAAUUUGAGACUUGAUUCCAUAUUAUUGCCUUAAAGGCUAUUAAAUUGGGUGACUUUUAGUAUCCAGCUGUUAAAAAGAGGAAAGACUGUUUAAUAUCAUUCCAAAAUUUUUGUGAAAUGUGGCCCAAGAUCUAAAGUUUUUAAGGGAAUUAUUUUUAAUAAAUAUGAUCUGUCCCUUUUUGAAAAGGAUCCAUCCCUUUUCAUAAUAAAAAUAAUUCCCUCCUACCACCCAGUUGCACAUACUUGCAUCUGUUAUGUAUUGAAGGAUAAUCCCCCCCAAAAAAACUAUCCAAGAGCAGAGAUGUUUAUAUUUUGAAACCCAUUUGAGUGUUACAGUAUUAUAUGACUAAAGCUGAAUCAGUCUGUGGCCUGGUAUUUGUUAUCAUAAAGGAAGAUGUACACCUAAGGUAUCAAGUGGUUAAAACAGCAAAGUACAAGAUGCAUUUUUGUAUUUAUUCUAACUUUUGAACAUUAGUGUCUUUCAGUAUAAAUAAAUGUGAACAAAUAUACCUCAGUAGUAAUACAGGAGAACUAAAUAUCCUGCUAUAACUUAAUACAGAUACAUAUUUCAAUAUGACUUAACAAACACACAAUUUUGAAAAAAAAAAAAAAAAAGUGCAGCAACUUAAACACAUUUUUCUCCCCAGAACUAAGAUUACACUUAAUUUAAUUUAAUGUGUUUCUGCGUUAUACUAGAGUUUUGCAGGAAUUUUUCUGAAUAGUACAUUCACAUGAUAGAUACGGAUAAAUACCUUAUUUACUAAAAUGUUUUGAAACAUAUUUUAUAGUCCCUCAUUUGAUUUGAAAAAAUUUGACAAGAUCUUCACAUUGAAAGUAAGGACGAGAAUAUUUGCAGAUUUCCUUCGUUCCAAAAUUAUUUUAUUCCAAAGAAAAAUUGAGUUGCCACUAUCAGGAAAAAAAAAAUGUAUCACUUCUGUUAGAAGGCUAUGAAGUAUAUAUAAAUUAUAUGACAAUUUUUAUCAUAUAGAUUUGAUAUCUUCUAUGUAUUCGUAUUUUUGCAUCUUGGGUAUUAAGCAAAAUACCAUAUGUAUAAAUAUGAAACCAGGAAUGUGCAUAUUUUAGAAACUAAUUGUGUAUCUUAAGUGAAUGUUUUGAGUAGUUCUGUCACCCCUAUUCUAAAUAUUUUACCUACAACAUUUAAAUUAUUCUGAUAUCAAUCAGAUAAAUAAUCCGAGUGUAUUUCAUCUUUCUACAUUGUCUUUGUGGUUUUUGUUUGUUUGUUUUUGAGACGGUCUCACACUGUCACCCAGGCUGGAGUGCAGUGGUGCAAUCUCAGCUCACUGCAACCUCCACCUCCCAGGUUCCAGCUAUCCUCCCACCUCAGCCUCCCAAGUAGCUAGGACUACAGGUGUGCACCACCAUGCCCAGCUAAUUUUUUGUCUUUUUGAUGUAGAUGGGGUUACCCCAUGUUGCCCAGGCUGGUUGUGAACUCCUGAGCUCAAGGGAUCCCCCCGCCUCUUGCCUCCCAAAGUGCUUGGAUUACAGGUGUGAGCCACCAUACCACCUGUCUUUGAAUUUUUUAACGAGGGGAAAGAAAACUGCAAUUCCUGCCUCCCCAUUUAUUUAAACAUAACACCUAGGAUUUUAUUUUUGGUAACUACUUAGAAUAAUAUAGUAGGUUACUUAUCUUCGGUUAGAAAGAACUAUGGAAAAUAGGAACCAAUAAUUUGGAAGUAUUAUUUCCUUAUUUCAUAUAUAGAAAUAAUUAUCUUAUUUCCUUAUUUCAUAUAUAGAAUAUUCUAGAUACUUGGAUGGCUGGGGUUGAUGUUCUUAGUAUUUAUCAUAGUUUAGCAUUGGUUGUUAUUUUUAAGCAUCAGAAUUUGAAAGCCAAUGAUAAUACCUGAUUAGGACUGAAAAUAGAAUUAUCUUAGUAGUUUAGCACUUUUUAUAAUGGAGUUGGAGCACUGAAUUUAUUUUCAAAUUACCUAGAAUUCUGCAUUGCUCAAACAUUAUUCAAUUGAUUGCAAAAUAUACCUUGGAAACCCUUUGGAUAGAACAGUUCAGAGGGUUACCACUAGUACUUAGAGCCUAAAGUCACUCAGUAGGAGGUUCUCAAAGGUCUAUUUGAAGGCAAUCCAAUUUCUUUAAAAUAAAAUAUUUUUUGCCUUUUAAAACAGAUGGGUGAAGAAAGGGACGUAUAAAUUCUGGGAAACCUCUUAUGUUUUCCUCCCAUUUCCUUCUAUGUCUCCAUUAAUGUGCUAACUUGAAGGAAUUUAACUUCAAGGAAAGUUGACUGAUGAAGUUUAUGUAGAGCUGUGAAUAUUAUAAUUUGUCAAUACUUUAUUGAUAAUGUUAACUUUGUUUUUAUUUGGAAACAUUUUUUCCAGUUGACCAAAGCAGAAUUCAUUCUGUUCUUCCCUCAAAUUCAUCUAUUAGGAUCAAUGUGAUUGACAUUUAUCUCCACUCUGCAUGUCACUGAUAUGGUAUAGACGCUAUAAGCCCUGUAGAUAUUAUGGGUAUGAAGACUAUUUGAGGUGAAUUGGCAGUGAGAGCAAAUUUUGGAAACAGGAGAGAGAACUACUUCGUGCCUAUAAAAAGCUCUCUCACUCCUUCCCCAAGAAAACAGGAGUCUGAAUUUUGGCCAGCUGGGUAUUUGAAUCUUACUGACUGUUGCAGCACUGGUAGUCCUGGUAAAUUUUUUCAGUGGGCGAGCUUUUCUGAAAUUUGAUUAAACAUAUUAGUCAAGGGAAUCUGUGAAUAGAUUUAGAAGUAGAAUGUUUGAGGUGGUUGACAAGACAUUUAGAAUUGUGAUUAAUGUUUUAAUAAAAUGCUAAGUUAGAAUGAAUAAUCAUAAUUAUAUAGAUGGAAGAUAUAUUCUAACAGUUCUUAAAUAAUUUUAGAUUCUCUAAAUUUAGAGUGUUUUCUAGCUUAGAGAGCAAUAUUAAUAUUUUUUACCUAGUCUACUGAACAUAAUUUCAGGGAGUUAGUAUUUAGGACUUUUUACCUAGAGAUGCGGUAAACCUUUUAAAUUUAAAUUUGCUUUCUUAAAAUACCUGUUCCAACAUUGCUCACCUUUCUUCUCCCUCCUUUUUGCCCUCUCCUUCAGUGGGAGGAGCACAUAUUCAGCUUUCUGUUAAACACUCUUUGGUUUUCAACUGAGUAAGGCAAGCAAGGAUAUAUGUUAGAAGAGUGGGCAUAAUACUUUAUAUUAAAAUUAUAGGGACUAAAAGUCUAAAUCAUUGCUGUCAAUAGGACUUUUUUUGAUGAUGGAAAUAAUUUAUGUCUGUGCUGUUCAAUAUGGUAGCCACUCGCAGAGGUGACUACUGAGCAUUUCACGUGUGGCUUGUGAUACAGAGGAACUAAAUUUUUAAUUUUACUUAAUUACUUUAAAUUUUAAAAGUUACACGUGGCUAGUGGGUCUAUCCCAACUAUGAAGAGAAUAAAGCUACAGAGCAUCUAUCUAGUCUAAUGAAACAACAGUGAAUUUGGGAAUUGUAAAUCUGUCUUAAGCUUUUUCCAUAAACUUUUAUUGAUAUAAUUUAGGCAUAUACAAAUACUGGUGAAAUUUUAUUGAUUGAAUUAUUGUUGACUUUUUUUUCAGUAUUUAUAUUUUUAAAAAGAUAUGUUUCUUUAUAAUUAACUUGUAUUGUAGGGUAACCAUUGUCCUUAAAUGUUAAGCCACUUAGUUAAUAACAAAUAGCAUUUGGUUUUUUAGCAUUAUUUAUCAUCUGAGGCUUUCAGAAUUAAUGCACCAAACCUUAAAUAUUUUUGUUGUUCUCUAAAAGAAUGGGUUUAUGAUGCACCAAAAGGACAUUUUGAGAACUGCCGGAGCAACAGAUACCACCAUGUAAGGAGUGAAUUCCCAUGUUUUUCACUUAUAUCUAGAGGCCUACUUAUUUAGGAGGUUUCCUAAGUAAGUGUAUUUAGUUGUAGGACCUUAGAGUUGCCUAGGUCCAUUCUAUUCUAGCAUAUACUCAACAUACUGCCAGAGCAAAUGUAGGUUGCAGAUUCAGGCAAAACACACACACACACACACACAAAACCCUGAAGAGCACAAUGAGCAUUAUUAGCACAGCCAAUUUAAAAUGAUGAGGUGUUAACCACAUUUGUAUAAAUAAUAGUUUCUCUAACCCUGAAUCAUUAUCCUGCAUUUUUAAUGCAAUCGGUUCAUAAACAUCAAAGUGAAAACACCAAAUUUGUAAGAGGUCAGGACCAACUGGGGCUCUAAAUGGAGAGACAGCUGAGAGCUGUGUCCCUAUGCGUGGGUGGCCUUGCAGCUGUUGAUUCACCCUCAGGCUACCAGACAGUUGCCUCUUUGCAUUUGCAGAACCAGACUUCAAUCUUAGGUAAAAAUGUAUCCCUCCCAUGGACAGGACAUAAACAAUAGAUUGACAUCAGCUCUGAAAACAGUGCAGCAGCCAGACUCAGCAGUUGCCCUGAAAUACUGAGAAGUACCAAGCAUAACAUCAAGACUGUUUCUACACAAUAAUAUUUGUCUUUGUACAGCAACACUGGGUUCUCUUAAGUAUAUUAUAAAUAUAAAAGCUCAAAGUCCAAAAGGUUCAAUGUGAUGAUAUCCUUCUCUACAAAUGCCAGGAACACCAGGGUAGAUUGCAUGAGACAUGACUGCCGUAUCUUGGUCCUUACUAGGAUUCCCAAAUAUACUCCUUAAUAACCAGUAAAGUUAUAUUUACACUGGACAUUUUAAGAAAUACCAGUGUUCGUUGUUAGAUGAGAGACAGCAUAAUUUUGGAAUCACAACUGAGUUCAGAGUUCAGUUUUGAGUCCUACUAGUUUUGUUUCCUUGUGUAAGUUUCUUAACCUUUGUAAGGCUAGCAUGUAAAUCAGAUACAAUAAUAUAUAGUUCAGGGUGUAAAGAUUGGAUUAAUGUAUGCAGUGUCUAUCUAGCACAGUGCCUGUUAUGUAGUAGCGUGUCAAGAGAUGUUCUCUCUUAUGCAUUUGGAGGAUUAGGUGCUGCACCUAUAGGUUUCCAUUCAUUUCUCAUCUAUGUAAUUCUGAGUCUUCCUUUUCUAGAUAGAAUUCCCCCCAACAAAAAUUUAAAGUCUAACAGGUGGUAGGUGCUUAUUGAGGCCCAGCAAUUCUACUUCUGGAAACCUUCCUCAGGAAAAGAUUCUGAUGACAGAAAAUGCUGUGUGAACAGUAUUAUAUAGAAUUGUUUUUAAUAGCAAGAAAUUUUUUAAAACUUACAAGUUCAGUGAUAUGAGGACAUUUACAUAAACUAUCGAACCACCAGUCUUCUGUCAAUUCCUUUUAAAAUGAUGGUUGUGAAGACUGAUGAAAACACAGUGUCAAUGAUAUGUUAACUGAAAAAGUAAGAUUAAAAACAUUAUGGAUAGUAUAAGUUUCUUAAAUGCCAACAAUGCAUGAGGUGAAUAGAAUAAGACUUUUUUUUAAAGAAUGUAAUUUUUGACAGUCUGAAAAGACAGGCCUUAUAUUUAUAUUGAGAAAAAUGAUCCUGACAUUUAAUGAGACACUAAAACAGUUUUUAUUUUUUGCUUACUUAUUCUGUUCUAGAAUCCAAACUCUACAUACUGUUUAAUAGAGCAUUAUUGAUAUUAGCUGUAUUAGAUGACUGUAUGAAGAGUCCUGUUUGCUAGAAUCCUACUUUAUCUUUUAAGUUUUGCUAAUUACCCUGCAAUGAAUGUUGAACAUAAAAAAUUUGACUCCCUUUCCAUGUGUCCACUGUUUCCUUGUGCCUUUUGAUUAAUAAAACUUUAUUUUUAAGUGAGAA